GACCAUUUAGCUUCUGUUGUUAAGUGGAUCUAAGCCUAUGUCGCUUACUGGACGCUGAAGUGAUUGGGAAUAUUAGCAGUGGGGGUUCUGUAGGGUCAGGAAGGGGCGGCUGGCUUUGGGGGAGUGAUGAGGGGCUUGUUGGGGGUGGGGGUGCGUGAUAAAGGGAUUUCUCGGCUGAAGACGAGGCUGUGAGGCUUCUGCAGAACCCCCAGGUCAGGCCACAUCAUUGAGGCUGCAGGAUCUCUCUUCAUAGCCCAGUACGACUCUCCGCCGUGUCCCUGGUUGGAAAAUCCAAACACCUAUCCAGCUUCUGGCUCCUGGGAAAAGUGGAGUUGUCAGCAAGAGAGACCGAGAGUAGAAGCCCAGAGUGGAGAUGCCUGCUGAUGUGAAUUUAUCCCAGAAGCCUCAGGUCCUGGGUCCAGAGAAGCAGGAUGGAUCUUGCGAGGCAUCAGUGUCAUUUGAGGACGUGACCGUGGACUUCAGCAGGGAGGAGUGGCAGCAACUGGACCCUGCCCAGAGAUGCCUGUACCGGGAUGUGAUGCUGGAGCUCUAUAGCCAUCUCUUCGCAGUGGGGUAUCACAUUCCCAACCCAGAGGUCAUCUUCAGAAUGCUAAAAGAAAAGGAGCCGCGUGUGGAGGAGGCUGAAGUCUCACAUCAGAGGUGUCAAGAAAGGGAGUUUGGGCUUGAAAUCCCACAAAAGGAGAUUUCUAAGAAAGCUUCAUUUCAAAAGGAUAUGGUAGGUGAGUUCACAAGAGAUGGUUCAUGGUGUUCCAUUUUAGAAGAACUGAGGCUGGAUGCUGACCGCACAAAGAAAGAUGAGCAAAAUCAAAUUCAACCCAUGAGUCACAGUGCUUUCUUCAACAAGAAAACAUUGAACACAGAAAGCAAUUGUGAAUAUAAGGACCCUGGGAAAAUGAUUCGCACGAGGCCCCACCUUGCUUCUUCACAGAAACAACCUCAGAAAUGUUGCUUAUUUACAGAAAGUUUGAAGCUGAACCUAGAAGUGAACGGUCAGAAUGAAAGCAAUGACACAGAACAGCUUGAUGACGUUGUUGGGUCUGGUCAGCUAUUCAGCCAUAGCUCUUCUGAUGCCUGCAGCAAGAAUAUUCAUACAGGAGAGACAUUUUGCAAAGGUAACCAGUGUAGAAAAGUCUGUGGCCAUAAACAGUCACUCAAGCAACAUCAAAUUCAUACUCAGAAGAAACCAGAUGGAUGUUCUGAAUGUGGGGGGAGCUUCACCCAGAAGUCACACCUCUUUGCCCAACAGAGAAUUCAUAGUGUAGGAAACCUCCAUGAAUGUGGCAAAUGUGGAAAAGCCUUCAUGCCACAACUAAAACUCAGUGUAUAUCUGACAGAUCAUACAGGUGAUAUACCCUGUAUAUGCAAGGAAUGUGGGAAGGUCUUUAUUCAGAGAUCAGAAUUGCUUACGCACCAGAAAACACACACUAGAAAGAAGCCCUAUAAAUGCCAUGACUGUGGAAAAGCCUUUUUCCAGAUGUUAUCUCUCUUCAGACAUCAGAGAACUCACAGUAGAGAAAAACUCUAUGAAUGCAGUGAAUGUGGCAAAGGCUUCUCCCAAAACUCAACCCUCAUUAUACAUCAGAAAAUUCAUACUGGUGAGAGACAGUAUGCAUGCAGUGAAUGUGGGAAAGCCUUUACCCAGAAGUCAACACUCAGCUUGCACCAGAGAAUCCACUCAGGGCAGAAGUCCUAUGUGUGUAUCGAAUGCGGGCAGGCCUUCAUCCAGAAGGCACACCUGAUUGUCCAUCAAAGAAGCCACACAGGAGAAAAACCUUAUCAGUGCCACAACUGUGGGAAAUCCUUCAUUUCCAAGUCACAGCUUGAUAUACAUCAUCGAAUUCAUACAGGGGAGAAACCUUAUGAAUGCAGUGACUGUGGAAAAACCUUCACCCAAAAGUCACACCUGAAUAUACACCAGAAAAUUCAUACUGGAGAAAGACACCAUGUAUGCAGUGAAUGCGGGAAAGCCUUCAACCAGAAGUCAAUACUCAGCAUGCAUCAGAGAAUUCACACCGGAGAGAAGCCUUACAAAUGCAGUGAAUGUGGGAAAGCCUUCACUUCUAAGUCUCAAUUCAAAGAGCAUCAGCGAAUUCACACGGGUGAGAAACCCUAUGUGUGCACUGAAUGUGGGAAGGCCUUCAACGGCAGGUCAAAUUUCCAUAAACAUCAAAUAACUCACACUAGAGAGAGGCCUUUUGUCUGUUACAAAUGUGGGAAGGCUUUUGUCCAGAAAUCAGAGUUGAUUACCCAUCAAAGAACUCACAUGGGAGAGAAACCCUAUGAAUGCCUUGACUGUGGGAAAUCGUUCAGUAAGAAACCACAACUCAAGGUGCAUCAGCGAAUUCACACGGGAGAAAGACCUUAUGUGUGUUCUGAAUGUGGAAAGGCCUUCAACAACAGGUCAAACUUCAAUAAACACCAAACAACUCAUACCAGAGACAAAUCUUACAAAUGCAGUUAUUCUGUGAAAGGCUUUACCAAGCAAUGAAUUCCUAGUGCAUCAGCAUAUUCAUAAAUGAAAUAUACUCCGAGUUUCUUGAAGAAGAGAAAAUCUUCUCAGAAUCAGGUCUAAUUAUAUGUUAUUGAAUUCAUGCUUCAGAAAAACUCUAGGGAUGCACUGCAUGUGUGAACACAUGAUAAAAAAGUCAUGCUUUAUUUUAGUGAGGGCAAUUACAGAGAAAAGAGUAAGCAGAAAUGUCCUUCUGAGUACUGGCCUCAUUAAGGAUUAUAAAUUUUCUCCCCGGGAAGAAACCCUGACUAACGCAUUGAGAAAAGCCUUUCUGUAAAGAAUGGUACAAGACAGGUUGUUACUCGAUUAUUUAUAGUAAAAUAUGUGGGAAAUUAUAUCAAUGAUAACCCUGUUUAUUGUGGGAUAUCAAUAUUUUUAAAGUGCCAACACAGUCAUGAUAGGACAAUAUUUUAUGUGUGUGUGUGCGCCUUAUGUAUAUAAGCAUAUAUAUAAUAUAUAAGCAUAUUAUUAUAUACAGGUUGAGUAUCCCUUCUCCAAAAUGCCUGGGAUCAGAAGCAUUUUGGAUUUCAGAUACUUACAGAUUUUGGAAUAUUUGCAUUAUAUUUAUUGGUUGAGCAUCCCUAAUCUGAAAAUCCAAGAUUAAAUGCUCCAAUUAGCAUUUCCUUUGAGCGUCAUGUUAGAGUUCAAAAAGUUUCAGAUUUUGGGUUUUCAGAUUAGGAAUACCCAACCUGUAUGUACGUAUAUUUCUGUAUCUAUGUAUGUAUAUAUAUGCAUAUGCAGACAUAUGUAUAUGGUCUGGUCAGCAUAUGUGUAUGUAUGCGUAUGUAUGUAUGUAUGUAUGCCCUCAGUGCAGUGGGGUUUGCUGCAGAAUUCACUGCAUAGCAGGAGAUGUAAGCAGAUGAGUUAUUUUUUAAGAGAAUCUAAUCUAAUUGUUUUUAUAAAAAUUAUUCCCUAUUGAAUAUUUAUAUAAUGAGGUUGUAUCAACAAUGAUUAACUCCUUUAUUAUACAUACACAUGAAUGUGCAUUUUUGGUAAAUGCAUAAAUGAGAUUCUAUAAUGUUUACUGAUCUUUAUAUUACAGAUUUUCUCUUCUUUUAGGAUUAGCUCAGCUUGCCCCCCCUUUCCAUCUCCACCAUCUAUAGUGAGCCUCUCCAUAAUUAGUGCCAACCAUUAGUCUCGUUCAUAUUUUUACACCAGGAGUCAACAAACUGUGGCCAUUGGCCAAAUAUGGCCUCCCAACUGUUUUUUUAAAAUAAAGUUUUAUUGGAACACAGCCAUGUUCAUUUGGACAUGUAUUGUCUGGGCUUCUUUUGUGCUGCACUGGCAGAAUUGAGUAGUUUUGGCGGAGAUCAAAUAGCCCCCAAGCUGGAAACUGAAAAUAUCUACUCUCUGGCUCUUUACAGAAAAUGUUUGCCAGCACAUGAUACACACACAAACACACACACAUACACACAUAUUACUAUGUUCAUCAUCAUAUACCUGUGUAAGUACUCUUUCAUUGAUUUAUAAAACUCAGAUCUCUUACGUGUGUGGAUGGUAUUUUUUUCAUUCUACAAUCCAUGAUGGAUUGUACACACGUGUAUUCUAUGAGGUUGACCUGCCAUAAUUUAUUUAGCCAUUCCCACAGUUUUGAUUACUUAUUUCCUCCCCACACACAUUUUUUGCUAAAAAACGGAGAGGGAACUGUUAUCAAUACUUCCGAGAAGCAGACCAGCAUAAUCUUUUAAGUGCACAGGCCCAGGAGCCAGGUUCCUGCAUUUGAUUCCUGGCUCCACUCUCUACCCUCUGCAUCUGCUGAGCAAGUUAUUUGGUCUCAUCUAUUCUGGUUUUCUCAUCUACAAAAGGGAGAUGAUGAUAGUACCCUACCCCCAUGCAUUUGGUGUGAGAAGUGUGUGUGUGUUAAACCCUUGGAACUGCAUGGACAGACCAAGUGCUGAUGAAUUUUAGCGGGCCUCGUAUCCCUGAGCCUGCCUGGUUCCCUUGUGCUGGGUGUGGGACUGUGGUGGGAGAUUUCUGUCAGCUGGAAGUCUUUUCCAGAAGGGUGUUAGAGAUGGGCACCCAUGGCUUUAGUCUCCAUACCCCUUCAAGGUUGAUAGGGGCCCACACAGCUGGUCAGGAACCAGCACAGACCUCAGGCUGUGUCUAAAACAAGGUGACUGCACAUGCAGGAGCCUGUGCUGGGCCCUGGAGAGCAAAUCUGUUCUGUGUCUCACUGGCCUCUCCCUGUCCAGGGGCGUAGUAUCAGUGACCAUGUCCCACCUCCUGAGAAAGGUGGAAGAGUCUCACCUGGGGAGUCCAGGUACAAGGGCUGGCCGGCCGUAGAUGACUGGUGUGGGGUGGAAAGGCUGCAGAGGCCUCUCCAUGGUGGUGAGGGGUGGAAAUAGUGUGCACCUGGGUCCUGGGAGUGGCACCCUGACCAGUUUCAGGGAGGAAGGUGGCAGGGCCCUAGGACAAGUGUGUUAAAAACUUGAGCCCACAGUGUAGACACACUGGUUCCAAAGACCCCUCAGGAUGUGCCUCCCUUCUCAGAUCUGGGCUUUCCCUGUUCCUAAGCAUCACCUGGGGGGAUCACUCUGGGUCCUCAUCUCCAGCCACAUGUUCACUCCUCACGUGGGCCUCCCUAACUGUCCCCCUCAGGGCAAGCCCUUCCUCCCCACUUCCAGAAAGCUGCUCGUUCCCUGGCCAUCCCACACCUCUGACCUCGUGCCACUUCCGGGGCCUGUUGGCUUUAACAACUUAGUUUCCUCCCUACCUCGCAACCCCCUCUGUCUAGAGUGCUCACCUCCCUCCCAGCCUCUGUCUCAUACUAUUUUUUCUUUCCUCUCAGUACCAAGCGCUGGGACAAGCCAGUCUGUACUCAAUGCCUGUGGGAUAAUAGACGGAGGAAUCUGGAGUUUGGUUGGGUGAUUAGCUUUGGAAUUGAUGGGUCCCAGGGAGCUAUCUAAAGUUUUCAGUCACAUGAGGGCAUGCUCACAGAUCUGUGAAAAGAUCUGUUGGCUCAGAGAACUAAGAGAUGAAUAAAUGUUAGUCCAAUGGCCUCAUCAUGAGAUGAGAGGUCAAGAGUUUUGAGUUUCCAGAGGGAGAAGCUACUAUUCUAGGCAGCUUGUAUGAACUAACUCGUUUAUUCCUCACAGCCAUUGUAGGAAAUAAUCUAACCUCAUAAACCCCAUUUUAGAGAUGAGGAAACAGGCUUAGAGAAUUUGACGUAAACUCAAGACCGAAAAUCUAGGAACAAGAAAAGCCUGGAUUUGAACCAAGCUAUCUGAUGCCAGUGUUUUAACUCUCAACCAUUGUACUACUUUACCUCCUCAUGACCUUUUUUUUUUUUUUCUUGUGAGAUGGAGUCUCGCUCUGUCGCCCAGGCUCUGGAGUGCAGUGGCACGAUCUCAGCUCACUGCAAGCUCCGCCUCCCGGGUUCACGCCAUUCUCCUGCCUCAGCCUCCCGAGUAGCUGGGACUACAGGCGCCCACCACCAUGCCUGGCUAAUUUUUUGUAUUUUUAGUAGAGACGGGGUUUCACCGUGUUGGCCAGGAUGGUCUCGAUCUCCUGACCUCGUGAUCCCCCCCCCUCGGCCUCCCAAAGUGCCCAUGACCUUUUUAUUGUUGGGCAGUGAAAGCCAUGGUGAAAUGAAGAAUGUCCUACUGUCAUGUGAUGUGAUCAGAAAACAUACUGCCCAGAGUCCCCUGCCCCCACCCCCAAAACCAGUACUUGAUCCAUCCUUUGACUGUUGUGGCGAUUGGCACAAAGGUUGGGCACAGUAGUAGUUAGGCUCAUGGGCUCUGGAGCCAACCUACCUGGAUGCUACACAUCCCAGCUCUGCCCCUCGCUAGUUUGGUGGCAAGCAACUUAACCUCUCUGCCUUAAUUUCUCCAGCAGCACAAUGGGAAUAAUAAUAGAUCUCGCCUUGUGGCUCCUUUGCAGAUUACAUGCGUUAAUUAUGUAAAGUCAAGCAUUAGAAUGGUGGCUGUCCACCAUGAGUACAACACAAAUGCUCGUUCUUAAUGAUUCAACAAACAUGGAAUUUCAUUAAAUCUGAAAUAAAGGUAUUUUGAGAAAUUGAA